GCAUUGGCUGUGCGGGGUGCGGGCGCGCGGGCGGCGCUUUGAACCGGGCGCGGGGCGCGGGGCGCGGGGCGCUGCGGCCGGUACACGCCGGGGUAGGGCCGGGGUCGGGUUGUGGUCGGGCCGGGAUUGGGCUCUCCUGGGCCAUGGCAGCCGAGGCGCGCGUGUCGCGCUGGUACUUCGGGGGGCUGGCCUCCUGCGGGGCCGCCUGCUGCACGCACCCGCUGGACCUGCUCAAGGUGCAUCUGCAGACGCAGCAGGAGGUGAAGCUGCGCAUGACGGGCAUGGCGCUGCGGGUGGUGCGUACCGACGGCAUCCUGGCACUCUACAGCGGCCUGAGCGCCUCGCUGUGCAGACAGAUGACCUACUCCCUGACUCGGUUCGCCAUCUACGAGACUGUGCGGGACCGUGUGGCCAAGGGCAGCCAGGGGCCUCUCCCCUUCCACGAGAAGGUGUUGCUGGGCUCCGUCAGCGGUUUAGCUGGAGGCUUCGUGGGGACGCCCGCAGACUUGGUCAACGUCAGGAUGCAGAACGACGUGAAGCUGCCCCAGGGUCAGCGGCGCAACUACGCCCAUGCGCUGGAUGGCCUGUACCGCGUAGCUCGUGAAGAGGGUCUCAGGAGACUGUUCUCGGGUGCAACCAUGGCAUCCAGCCGAGGGGCCUUAGUCACUGUGGGCCAGCUGUCCUGCUACGACCAGGCCAAGCAGCUGGUCCUUAGCACCGGGUACCUCUCUGACAACAUCUUCACUCACUUUGUCGCCAGCUUUAUUGCAGCCGCUGGUGACGAGCCCCCUCCUCAGGGUGGAUGUGCCACGUUCCUGUGCCAGCCCCUGGAUGUGCUGAAGACUCGCCUGAUGAACUCCAAGGGGGAGUAUCAGGGCGUUUUCCACUGCGCCGUGGAGACAGCGAAGCUCGGGCCUCUGGCCUUUUACAAGGGCCUCGUCCCAGCUGGCAUCCGCCUCAUCCCCCACACCGUGCUCACUUUUGUGUUUCUGGAACAGCUACGCAAAAACUUUGGCAUCAAAGUGCCAUCCUGACCAGCCGUGGGAAUGGCUGGGCUGCCAGGCCAGACACGCUAGGUUCUUCCAAAGAGUCCCAAGCCCAGCACCUGCUCCUGGGGCCACGACCUCCCUGGCCGUGGCCACCCGUCCUCCGCAGCAGGCCCCUGCUGUCCCCCCACCUGCUGGCUGAGCUCCUCCUGGCCUCGUCCCCUCUCAGCUGUAGCUGCACCACCCCCGCUCUGGCUACCAGGCUCUCCCGGCUGGGCACUGCGUGGCCUUGCCCCUCUCCCGCUGGCAGCUCCUCAGGGGAACAGGGGCUACCAGAGGCUGAUUUCUCCCCUCUCCUGGGCCAGGGGAGGGGUAUUAUCCCUGCCUCCUGCCCCCGAUGCCCAAAGCAGCAUCUUCCAGCACUUUCCAUCGAGGACUUGGGUGGCAGAGUGUGGGUGCAGCCUGGCUGUUGCUCACCCAAGUGCUAGCUCUGCACUUCGUGUCUGCUGAGAGCAACCAGACCUUCCAUGUCCUCGGGCAGCUGCAACUCCCCGCGAGACCCCGCAGCUGGGUGGGAUGAACAAGCAACGCAGACCACAAGCGAGUGCCUGGGAGGGAGUGGCCCAGGGUGGUUCUGGAGCCAUUGUGGGUGAGGGUCGAGGGCCACCGAGGUCCCGCGCACCGCUGCCUGCCCUGCAGUGGCUUUAACAGUUAGUUUUGCCAAAGCCUCUCCACUCACCAGCAGGCGGUCUCUGUCUUCAGGGAUUGUGCCUGCGUCCCUCGGGCACCUGGGCCCCCCCGCUUGGCUCCCUGGGGGAAUGGCCCAGGCGGGCCGCGGUUCCUCCUUAGGGCCUUCUCCCCGACAAGGAGUCCGACGGGGCGGAUGCUGCAUCCUCUGCCUCCCUGGUCGCUGGGCUUCACCCCACCUGGGAAGGGCAGUGUGCUCUGUGGGGGCUGCAAUCAAUAAAUGCCGGGAGCUGCCA